GGCAGAGCCGCAGGUCAGUCGUGAAGAGGGAGCUCUAUUGCCACCAUGAGUUUCUCCGGCAAGUACCAACUGCAGAGCCAGGAAAACUUUGAAGCCUUCAUGAAGGCAAUCGGUCUGCCGGAAGAGCUCAUCCAGAAGGGGAAGGAUAUCAAGGGGGUGUCGGAAAUCGUGCAGAAUGGGAAGCACUUCAAGUUCACCAUCACCGCUGGGUCCAAAGUGAUCCAAAACGAAUUCACGGUGGGGGAGGAAUGUGAGCUGGAGACAAUGACAGGGGAGAAAGUCAAGACAGUGGUUCAGUUGGAAGGUGACAAUAAACUGGUGACAACUUUCAAAAACAUCAAGUCUGUGACCGAACUCAACGGCGACAUAAUCACCAAUACCAUGACAUUGGGUGACAUUGUCUUCAAGAGAAUCAGCAAGAGAAUUUAAACAAGUCUGCAUUUCAUAUUAUUUUAGUGUGUAAAAUUAAUGUAAUAAAGUGAACUUUGUUUUAAAAAAAAA